GUUGCUAGGAUACGACCAACAGCUGAGAACGCGGCGAGUAUGGAAGCUGCGUCUUAGGAGCCUGGGAAAGCACUUCGACGAGAAUAGUUUGGUUUCGUACACAGGAAAAUGUCUAAUCAACAGGAGAAGUAUGAAGCUCAGAAUAUAGUCAAUUCAACAGAAGAGAGUGAUGAUGCUUUUGAUACUGUCACUAUUCCAGUUCCCUCAGAAGAGCCUCAAGAGUCAGAUCAAACUGAAGAGCAUGAAUCUGGAAUAGAACAAUUCAGUGAGAGCCAUGCAAUACAUGUUGAGGAGCAGAGUGACCAAAGCUUUUCAAGCCUGGAACCAGACAAUGAACAACUCAUGGAAGAGGUUAUAUCACCAAGACAAGUUUCAUAUACUCCGCAACAUCAUGAAAAGCAAUAUGCAAUGCAGAGGCCAAAUGAUGAUAGUUUGGCAUUUCUGGAUAAAAUAAAGUCUGUAAAGGAAUCUUUGCAAGAAUCAGUGGAAGAUUCUCUAGCAACAGUAAAAGUUGUACUUAUUCCAGUGGGCCAGGAAAUUGUAAUACCUUUUAAGGUUGAUACCAUUCUUAAAUAUCUUAAGGACCAUUUUUCACACUUAUUAGGUAUCCCACAUUCUGUACUGCAGAUAAGAUACUCAGGAAAAAUUCUUAAAAAUAAUGAGACUCUAGUACAACAUGGAGUUAAGCCACAGGAAAUUGUACAAGUGGAAAUCUUUUCUACAAAUCCAGAUCUGUAUCCAGUCAGAAGAAUAGAUGGAUUAACUGAUGUCUCUCAAAUCAUAACUGUCACUGUCCAAACUGGACUUGAUCAAUACCAGCAGGUACCUGUUGAGAUUGUCAAAUCUGACUUUCACAAACCAUUUCUUGGUGGAUUCAGACAUAAAGUAACAGGAGUAGAGUAUCACAAUGCUGGAACACAAACUGUACCUAAAAGGAUUCCCGAAAGACUCAGUAUAUUUUGUAGGGAUACGCAGACAGUUUUUCAGAAAAAAAAUCUCCAACAAACUACAAAUACAACAUCCACACAGAUGACUAACAUUGGUGUAUAUGUAUCAAAUAUGACUGAUAAACUGGUAACACCAGGAAAGUAUUUUUCAGCAGCAGAAUACCAUGCUCAAAGACUAAAGGCGGUGAUAGUGAUACAGACUUACUACAGGCAAUGGCAUGCUAAAAUCUUCGUAGAGAAUUUAAGAAGACAGAAAAGCUUAAGACUGGAAUGGGAAACACAGCAAGAACUAAGGAAGAUAAGAGAAAAAGAAGAAUGGAUAAAAUUGGACUAUCACCGGAGGCAUAAUCCUAAAACAAAUGAAGAUUUUGAAUUUCUUUAUAAUGCAUUAGAAUUCUGGCGGCAAGAAGAACUUACACGUAUUAACCAAUCUUUUACUGGAGCUGAAAGGAAAGCUGCUCUGUGUGAACUUCUGGAAAAAGAGACUCAGAUAAUUGCUUCCAUUGGGAGACAUAGAUACAUUGCUUAUAUGGCAAAUCAGGAAGCAGCAAUACAAGCUUUUUUGGAUAAGUGUUCAGCUCCAAAAAUAUGGAGAACCCCUAAUGGCAAAACAAUUGAGAUGGAUACGCAGUUCACCAUCAGAGCCAGAGAGCUGCAAAAUAUCUAUAAGUGCAUUAUGCUGAAAAAUAUCUCCCAAGAUGAGAGGCUGGAUGUGCUGUUAACUCUUAAACACACUGUAAAGGAACAUGAAUGUAAACUAACUCAGGAAAUUCUAGAAUUGAUUGACAGAGAGGUUGACCUUAUGAUGAGAGGAGUCAAACAUCAUAACCUUGAAGGACUCAGAAAAAGAAUUGCGACACUCUUUUUUCAUUAUAUCAAAACACCUCUGUUUAAUCCUGAAGUUGCAAAAUACCUUAAGGUCCCUCAAGACCCAUUGAAAUUUUAUAAGAAGAUUUACUUUUGCCACAGUUGCCAGCUUUAUUUGCCUUCUACAGAAUUUUCUGUAUCAUCCACCUCACGCCGCAUAUACCGGUGUCGUAACUGCAUUAACCUUCAGAAUGAGGCUCAAAAACGAGAAUCAUUUUUGAAGUACAAAUGUUUACUUCAACAGCUCUACUAUACAGAAGCUGAUUAUGAAGAUGAUUCUAAAAUUGCUUUCUUGAUGCAGCUACAAGACAUUCAGUACCUGACAGAGAACAUCUGGGCGUCCCAGUCAGUCCUCAGUGCUUGCGACAAUCUCAGUGAUCUGGUCAUGGUCAGAUGGAAUAAAUCCCUGGAGUGGUCCCCCUGGAACUGCAUUCUUCUUACCAAAGAUGAAGCAGCUGCUCAUCUCAAGCUAACAAGUAUUGAAGAGAUUAAGAAACAGAACUUAUGGAUUAACAACAAAAAAAUUUAUGGAUGGCAUAUAUGGCACAGAUUAAAUAAAAGGUAUAUAUAAGAGAUUUGAACAUAUUACAAGUCCUAAACAUCAUACCAGUCUCUCCUAAUAGUAAGUUUAAGCACAUUCCACGGUAAAUUCCAUGAAGGCAGUGAUUUUGUUUGGCUUAUUUACAUCUAUUUCUCUAAUACCUACAAUACUGCCUGUCACAGAAUGGAGUUUAUAAGUAUUUGUUGAAUGAAUAAAUGUGCAUUACCACCAGAUAGGUAUUAUGGAACCCAGAAUCUGUCCUUCUUUGAUUAAUUAUCAUGAGUCUGCUUAAAAACACCCAACUCUCAAAUUUUGUUCAUAAUUUUGUGCUCUAAAUAGCAAUCAUACUGAUGGGGUGUAGUUCUGAUGCUCCAUUUUUCAUUUGCUUCCAACUUGCUGGGAGUGGAGCAAGCACUGUAAACAUUAAAUGCCAUUUACUGUAAUUUUAGUAACUUACAUGAUGCAAUCUGUAAAACAUUUUGAUGGGUAAGUUGAGGGACUCCUGAAGAGUUCGUAGAGAGCUCCAUUUACACUAGGUCCAGGAUCCCGAGAGUUAAUACUGAUUCUCUGCAUUCUUUAAUUCCACACAAGGUGUCAGCUAAAGGAAAGUAAAGAAAUGACAAAAUGCAGUAGUCGUUUAAAAUAGUGUGAUUCCCUGUUUGUUUUUUUUCAGUGGAACAAGGGGUGAUGAAUAUAAAGAUAAGAAACUAGCUAAAGUUUUAGUUUUUAAAUAUUUUUUUAGUUUUAAGAAGCCAGGCUAAGAAAAAUUUCACUCUAGGGAUUGAAAGAAAAGGUAGCAAUAAGUUGAAGCUGUAUUAAAUGUUAUAUUUAGUAAACUAAGCUGCCUCAUAAAUAUUUAAUCACAGGAAGCAUAGUCAAUACUAGCAAUAUCAUUUCAUCUAGGACCCAUGAUGAGAUUGAAGUUCAUUCCCAAAGCUGAUAUUCCAGUGCUUCUUCAAUUAAUCCACACAACUCCCUUUGUGCAUUUAAUCAAAUUACUGCAGUAUCAAAUUAAAUGUUCUAUUCACAUGCAUUUCUAAUUUAGAAUGCCAGUCUUAUCGAAUUUCUGUAAAGGGCACCAAGAUUUGCAAGCAGACAAACUGGAAAAACAUUUGCCUUUUUUAUGGUUUUGGGCUGAUACAAUCUUUUAACUAUUAACUUUCAGCCCAGUUAAAGAGUAGUUUAUAUCUUGCAGAAAGAUGGAGCAUUUUCAGAAUUUUCUUAAUGUUCAGAGAUAUUUGCUUUCUUAAGAAGUUAAAAAAAUACUUGCAAGUUAAUAUGAAACAGGUAUAGGAAACGUGGAAAAACACUUUCGUUAAUGUGAACUUUAAGUGGAGCAGAUUGAUCUCUCCUUGUGUGCACACUGGCCAAAGUAGGAACAAUCAUGGACUUAAAAUCAGUAAUCCUGACCCAGUUAACUCAAAUCUCUGUCACUGACAACUUUACAUUAAAACCUUCCCUCUUUGCUUCAUAAAUUUUUAGAAAGAUUAGCUAAAUAAGUGGAAUCAGUAAAGAGGAUAAAAGCAGCUCUGGCUCUGAAUUCUAGCUUUACCAUUCAUGAGCUGGGAGAAAUUGGACAAAUUUGUGAAUGUCUCAAUGACCCAGCUUUCUCGUCUAUAAAAAAGAGAUAAUGGUAUCUCAUCAUAGGGAAGCUUUGAGUAGGCCAUUAUUUAAAGCUUUCUGCAUAGUUUUUUUUGGCAUGAAUAAACUUAGGUAGUAACUAUGAAAGCACUUUAAAAAUUUUUGAUGCAUUUUAUUUUUAAUUUUAAAGCAAUAUAUUAUUGGCUUAGAAUCUGAACAGAAUAAAAAAUGUAAUGUAGAAAGUAAAGGUCUCAGAGGUUGAGGGAACAGGGAGAGAUUUGUUAAGGAUACAAAAAUUAUAGCUAGAUGGGAGGAGUGAGUUCUAGUACUGUUCUGUGGCACUGUAGGUUGUCUAUAGUUAAUUACAAUAUAUGGUUUCAAAUAGCUAGACGCAGCAUAUCGAAUGUUCCCAGCACAAAGAAAUGAUAAAUGUUUGAGAUGAAUAUGCUAAUUACUCUGAUCAUGAUAUAUGUAUCAUCCCAUCACUAUGUACCCCGUAAAUAUGUACAAUUAUUAUCAAUUUAAAAAAUUUAAAAAACGACUGAAUGAAUAAAUAAAGGGAGGCAAAUAGACAAAUCUCCCAUGUAGAAUUCCAAAUAAUUUAUGUAGAUACUCUCCACUCUUAAGGAGAUGGAGAAUAACUCUCUACCCUUUAAAUGUGGGCUGUACAUAAUAACUCCUUUCCAAAGACUAUAUUAUGGAUGGAAGGGGAGGACCUUUACAGUAGAGAAACUUGACAAACACUACCUCAGCCAGGUAAUCAAGAUUAACAGCAGCAGUGCUGUCAUGCUGAUGGUGUGUACCCUUGAUAUGAUGUGAGGAGAAGGGCACUUCACCCCUGUGGUCUUCCUCCCCAAAACCCAUCCCUUCAGUCUAAUAAUAAUGAAGAAAACACAGGACAAACCCAGAUUGAGACACAUUCAGGAAAAUGUGGGUGUGGGGUAUAUGGGACCUUUCUGUAAUAUUCUUAGAACUAUUUGUACACCCAAAGAAUUUGUGAACAUAGUUUAAAACCAUCACAUGGCUAUUUCAAGAGAAUGGACCUUAUUUCAAUGGGAAAAAAGGUCUCUUGAUGUCCACCCAUCCCUAUCUCCAUGUUGCAAUGAUAACUACUAUUUCUUAGGUAUAUAAUAAUCUAUUGAAAUCCUUCUGGAAGUUUUCUAUGUGUAUGUAAGUAUAUAUACUUUUACUGUAGCAGGAAUUUCAUAUUAAAUGACUCUGAGACUUAGUUUCUUUGCUUUACUUAACAAUAUAAAUAAUAUAAUAUGGAAAUAUAUUCAGUUAUUUAAGAGUUACUUAUUAGUGCCUUGAACACAUAUAUCAUAAUUUAUCUCAUCUUUAAUAAUUUAUAGUACUGUAAAGGCACCUUGAAAACCUAUAAAGUUCUGUACAUGUGUAAGUUAAUAUAGCAUAAUAAAGUGUGUUAGUUUUUCUUGAAUGAAAUAUGGGCUAAGAAGUGGUAGAAACAAAGUUAGAUUAGCUCAAAAGAUGAAUAUUUUAACCUAGUAAAUUUUUCUGUUAAGAGGAAAUUUUAAUAAGCCCAGGAUACUCCUAUAUAAUGUUUUCUGCUCUUUUGGUCCUUUCACCCAGGACUUUCUUUUAUCUUUGAUUUGACCCUCUGAAGAGACCUUUAUUGAGGGAAUGUCUUAUUCUCAGAAAAUAAAUUUUAGGAAGAAGUAUAGGUAGUAUUUGUGAUUUGAUUGAAAAGAGGGCCAAUUAAGAUUAAUAGGUAAUAGAUUAUAUUUAUUAAUUUAACCAGAAUUUACUUUUGAAUGUGCCAAAUACUGUACUAAGUAAUUACAGAGAAACAAGAAAAUUUAAUGAAUAUAACUUUUUGUUGUCUCAGUUGCAUUUAGGUUCAGCUACAAGAACAGAAAAAGCAAUUUAUAAUGAUUUAAUCAAAUGUGGGUUUAGUUUUCUUAUGUAACAAGAAAGUUCAAAGGUUGGCAGUUUGGGGCUAGUAUGGUGGCUCCACCUUGUUCUCAGAAAUUCAGGCCAUCUCACUUUUUCCUCAGCCAUAUUUAAUCUUCAGCUUUCUCUCUCAUGCUUGGUGGGCUCUUAGUGAUAGGAUAGCUAGUUCAUCUUCUUCAUUACAUGUACCUCUCAGUAAUGGCAAAAGGCUAGAGGUGCUUGAUAGGUGAGUCUUCCCACUCUCAAAAGUCCCUUUCAAAGGCUUUAUUCAAUUAUAUAUAUAUAAUUAUAUAAGGUUAUAUAUAUUGUGUAUAAUUAAAUAAUCUUGGAAGAUAUUUAGUUAUCUCCUUAGAUUCUUCUUGGUGGUGACAGUUUCUCAGACUUCCCUUGUUUUGUUUUGUUUUUAUUUUUGUUUUUUCUCACCUCAAUAUCUAUAACAUUAAUAAUAUAUAUAUAUAUAUAUAUAUUCUAACUAGAUACCCCCAGUUAGAAUAAGGGCUAAGAAAGCUAGACACAUCACACCCUAUACAAAAUCAGGCCUCUGGCUCAAAUGGGAGAAAGAAUGAAUAUUGAGUUGAUAACUAGCAGUGGUUUAAACUUAGAGAAGUCAGAGGGAGAGUUGGGGAAAACUUCCAGGUUAAAGUAUCAUAGGAGCUGAGUCGUGAAUGAUGAUAGACAACGUGAGAAAAAUAAAGGUAGUCUGGGAUGAAAGAAUUGACAAGCAAAGGCACCGAGGCAUGACAGUAUUUUUACCUGGCAAAAUAUAUCUGUGAUAUUUACUAGAAUUUGAUUUUUUUCU